ACUGGUCAGCUGGGGUCGCUCUCGGGUGGUUGGGUGUUGCUUGUUCCCGCUGUUCCAGCAUCGAAGAACCAUUGGGUCUGCCGGUUUGAACUUGUUCUGGAAGCUGUGCGUCACCGUAAUGAGGCUUGUAAUUCUUGAUAACUAUGACUUGGCUAGUGAAUGGGCAGCCAAAUACAUCUGUAAUCGCAUCAUUCAGUUCAAACCUGGACAGGACAGAUAUUUUACACUGGGUUUACCAACAGGGAGUACACCUUUAGGAUGCUAUAAAAAACUAAUAGAAUAUCAUAAGAAUGGACACCUUUCUUUUAAAUAUGUGAAGACCUUUAAUAUGGAUGAAUAUGUAGGACUUCCAAGAAAUCAUCCUGAAAGCUACCAUUCUUAUAUGUGGAAUAAUUUUUUUAAGCAUAUCGAUAUAGAUCCUAAUAAUGCACAUAUCCUUGACGGGAAUGCUGCAGAUUUACAAGCAGAAUGUGAUGCUUUUGAAAACAAAAUAAAAGAAGCUGGAGGAAUAGAUCUUUUUGUUGGAGGAAUUGGUCCAGAUGGUCAUAUCGCUUUCAAUGAGCCUGGAUCCAGUUUAGUGUCAAGGACAAGAUUAAAGACUCUAGCAAUGGAUACCAUCUUGGCAAAUGCCAAAUAUUUUGAUGGAGAUUUAUCAAAAGUGCCAACUAUGGCUCUAACUGUUGGUGUGGGGACAGUGAUGGAUGCUAGAGAAGUAAUGAUCCUUAUAACAGGGGCACACAAGGCAUUUGCCCUGUACAAAGCAAUAGAAGAAGGAGUCAAUCACAUGUGGACUGUUUCCGCUUUCCAGCAGCAUCCCCGGACUAUUUUUGUAUGCGAUGAAGAUGCUACUUUAGAAUUAAGAGUUAAAACUGUGAAAUACUUUAAAGGUCUAAUGCAUGUGCACAAUAAACUUGUGGAUCCACUAUUCAGUAUGAAAGAUGGAAACUGAAGGAGACUGGAGCAAAAUUCAGCUUGAAUGAACAGAGCACUUUUUACUAAGUAGUAGAUGAAUUUUCAGCUAUGCAAUAUGACAAAACAUGGGGAAUUUUGAAGAUUGUCAUUUUUUCAUUCGAGUCUCUAUGUUAAACAUUCCAUAUUUUGAAUAUUUAUAUCUUGUACUUGGGUUUAAGAGAAGUAGCUGGCUCUCAAGAUUGACUGGCUAUUUAUUAUAAAGUACUGAAGUCACAUAGCCACCUAUAAAACAGCAUAGAAAUGUCUGCCUGUUUAAAAAGUCAUUUUAAAGGUAGAGUGUCCACAUCAGGCACCAUUUGUGAUAUGACUCCAGUGGCGUAUAUUUCAUUUUUUAAUGACAAGACACUCCAAACCUUUCAGAUAACAAACUAUCAUUGCAGACCUUCACUUUUGGAAUGCAAUCUUUAUAUUUUCUGUGCAUCACACACAUGCUUUUCUGCACGUGGUUGCCUUAGUCAUCUUCCUACAGCACCAUCUAGACAUCAAAAAUUGUGCUAUAUAUCAUUGGUAAAGGAAAUUUGAAGAGAUGACAGUGCCUAAAAGUACAGUUUACAUCCUUUUGGAAAGUAUGUGUAAGUGCAUGUUUUUUGUGCACCUUCUUCUAUAGCACUUUUUUACAAAUAUCUUAUUUUUAUUUAACGACUUGGGUUCAUGUCCCUAAUAUAAGUAUCUUGACAAUUAUGAGCUUUAUACCUAGCAAGCCACUUCAGGAAAUUCUUUUGGAGAAUAUUUUCUGAUUAUUGUUAAACUUAAUAUACAAUUAGCUUUAUUCCUUAUAAAAUGUCUAAAAGAAUAAUACGAAGUAUAUAUAAAAGGAAUUACUGUAAACUACAUUGCCAUAGCAAUUUACAUAAAAGUAUAUUGUUUUUUAUCUUUAACUCAAAUAAAGCGUGUAAUAAAUAAGUUAUCUAAAUUUCCAGAAGUGAACCUGAAGAAUACAUGCAUUCGACUCCCAACAAUUAUAGUACAUGUGAACCUGCAUUCAUUUUGGGUUUGUUACCAUCAUGCAUUAGGAGAGUUAGGUUAAAAGAUGUCUUUGCCUCUGUGGGGAGCAAAAAAAUGCUCCUUUUGCUUAUUUUGCAUUUCAUAAGCCCACCUGGUAGAAGAAGCCUUACUUAUCUGCUUGUCUAUGUGAUUAAAAUGUAGUUUCUUAAAAUAUUAAAAUAGCAAAUAAAUUAAUGAAAUAAAAUUGGUAAUAGGGUUUUAUGGUUAAAAGUGGGGGAUGGGGUAAAUUAUGCUGCUUUAAUUCCAGAUGAUGUUUUA